GCAGAGCUCUGUGCUCCCUGCAGUCAGGACUCUGGGACCGCAGGGGGCUCCCGGACCCUGACUCUGCAGCCGAACCGGCACGGUUUCGUGGGGACCCAGGCUUGCAAAGUGACGGUCAUUUUCUCUUUCUUUCUCCCUCUUGAGUCCUUCUGAGAUGAUGGCUCUGGGCGCAGCGGGAGCUACCCGGGUCUUUGUCGCGAUGGUAGCGGCGGCUCUCGGCGGCCACCCUCUGCUGGGAGUGAGCGCCACCUUGAACUCGGUUCUCAAUUCCAACGCUAUCAAGAACCUGCCCCCACCGCUGGGCGGCGCUGCGGGGCACCCAGGCUCUGCAGUCAGCGCCGCGCCGGGAAUCCUGUACCCGGGCGGGAAUAAGUACCAGACCAUUGACAACUACCAGCCGUACCCGUGCGCAGAGGACGAGGAGUGCGGCACUGAUGAGUACUGCGCUAGUCCCACCCGCGGAGGGGACGCAGGCGUGCAAAUCUGUCUCGCCUGCAGGAAGCGCCGAAAACGCUGCAUGCGUCACGCUAUGUGCUGCCCCGGGAAUUACUGCAAAAAUGGAAUAUGUGUGUCUUCUGAUCAAAAUCAUUUCCGAGGAGAAAUUGAGGAAACCAUCACUGAAAGCUUUGGUAAUGAUCAUAGCACCUUGGAUGGGUAUUCCAGAAGAACCACCUUGUCUUCAAAAAUGUAUCACACCAAAGGACAAGAAGGUUCUGUUUGUCUCCGGUCAUCAGACUGUGCCUCAGGAUUGUGUUGUGCUAGACACUUCUGGUCCAAGAUCUGUAAACCUGUCCUGAAAGAAGGUCAAGUGUGUACCAAGCAUAGGAGAAAAGGCUCUCAUGGACUAGAAAUAUUCCAGCGUUGUUACUGUGGAGAAGGUCUGUCUUGCCGGAUACAGAAAGAUCACCAUCAAGCCAGUAAUUCUUCUAGGCUUCACACUUGUCAGAGACACUAAACCAGCUAUCCAAAUGCAGUGAACUCCUUUUAUAUAAUAGAUGCUAUGAAAACCUUUUAUGACCUUCAUCAACUCAAUCCUAAGGAUAUACAAGUUCUGUGGUUUCAGUUAAGCAUUCCAAUAACACCUUCCAAAAACCUGGAGUGUAAGAGCUUUGUUUCUUUAUGGAACUCCCCUGUGAUUGCAGUAAAUUACUGUAUUGUAAAUUCUCAGUGUGGCACUUACCUGUAAAUGCAAUGAAACUUUUAAUUAUUUUUCUAAAGGUGCUGCACUGCCUAUUUUUCCUCUUGUUAUGUAAAUUUUUGUACACAUUGAUUGUUAUCUUGACUGACAAAUAUUCUAUAUUGAACUGAAGUAAAUCAUUUCAGCUUAUAGUUCUUAAAAGCAUAACCCUUUACCCCAUUUAAUUCUAGAGUCUAGAACGCAAGGAUCUCUUGGAAUGACAAAUGAUAGGUACCUAAAAUGUAACAUGAAAAUACUAGCUUAUUUUCUGAAAUGUACUAUCUUAAUGCUUAAAUUAUAUUUCCCUUUAGGCUGUGAUAGUUUUUGAAAUAAAAUUUAACAUUUAAUAUCAUGAAAUGUUAUAAGUAGACAUACAUUUUGGGAUUGUGAUCUUAGAGGUUUGUGUGUGUGUACGUAUGUGUGUGUUCUACAAGAACGGAAGUGUGAUAUGUUUAAAGAUGAUCAGAGAAAAGACAGUGUCUAAAUAUAAGACAAUAUUGAUCAGCUCUAGAAUAACUUUAAAGAAAGACGUGUUCUGCAUUGAUAAACUCAAAUGAUCAUGGCAGAAUGAGAGUGAAUCUUACAUUACUACUUUCAAAAAUAGUUUCCAAUAAAUUAAUAAUACCUA